CUUUCUGUGCGGCGCCCGGGCGCAACGCAAACAUGGCGGCGGGUGGCACCCGUCGGUGAGGCGGUGCCGGGCGGGGGUUGUCGGGUGUCAUGGGCGGUGGCGACGGCACCGCCCCCGCGUCUCCCUGAGCGGGACGGCAGGGGGGGCUUCUGCGCUGAGCCGGGCGAUGGACGACAGCGGCGAGCUGGGUGGUCUGGAGACCAUGGAGACCCUCACGGAGCUGGGCGACGAGCUGACCCUGGGAGACAUCGACGAGAUGCUGCAAUUUGUCAGUAAUCAAGUGGGAGAGUUCCCUGACUUGUUUUCAGAACAGCUGUGUAGCUCCUUUCCUGGCAGUGGUGGUAGUGGUAGCAGCAGCGGCAGCAGUGGCAGCAGCAGCAGCAGCAGCAAUGGCAGGGGCAGCAGCAGCGGAGCUGUGGACCCUUCAGUGCAACGGUCAUUCACCCAGGUCACAUUACCUUCCUUCUCUCCCUCGGCGGCCUCCCCACAGGCUCCAACUCUGCAAGUCAAGGUUUCUCCCACCUCAGUUCCCACCACACCCAGGGCAACUCCUAUUCUUCAGCCCCGCCCCCAGCCCCAGCCUCAACCUCAAACUCAGCUGCAACAACAGACGGUAAUGAUCACGCCAACAUUCAGCACCACUCCGCAGACGAGGAUCAUCCAGCAGCCUUUGAUAUACCAGAAUGCAGCUACUAGCUUUCAAGUCCUUCAGCCUCAAGUCCAAAGCCUGGUGACAUCCUCCCAGGUACAGCCGGUCACCAUUCAGCAGCAGGUGCAGACAGUACAGGCCCAGCGGGUGCUGACACAAACGGCCAAUGGCACGCUGCAGACCCUUGCCCCGGCUACGGUGCAGACAGUUGCUGCGCCACAGGUGCAGCAGGUCCCGGUCCUGGUCCAGCCUCAGAUCAUCAAGACAGAUUCCCUUGUUUUGACCACACUGAAGACAGAUGGCAGCCCUGUUAUGGCUGCGGUCCAGAACCCGGCCCUCACCGCCCUCACCACCCCUAUCCAGACGGCUGCCCUUCAAGUACCAACCCUGGUGGGCAGCAGUGGGACCAUUCUGACCACAAUGCCUGUAAUGAUGGGGCAAGAGAAAGUGCCCAUUAAGCAGGUACCUGGGGGAGUCAAGCAGCUUGAGCCCCCCAAAGAAGGAGAAAGGCGGACAACCCAUAAUAUCAUUGAGAAACGAUAUCGCUCCUCCAUCAAUGACAAAAUCAUCGAAUUGAAAGACCUGGUCAUGGGGACAGACGCCAAGAUGCACAAGUCUGGCGUUCUGAGGAAGGCCAUUGAUUACAUCAAAUACUUGCAGCAGGUCAAUCAUAAACUGCGCCAGGAGAACAUGGUGCUGAAGCUGGCAAAUCAAAAGAACAAGCUUCUAAAGGGCAUCGACCUAGGCAGUCUGGUGGACAAUGAGGUGGACCUGAAGAUCGAGGACUUUAAUCAGAAUGUCCUUCUGAUGUCCCCCCCAGCCUCUGACUCAGGGUCCCAGGCUGGCUUCUCUCCCUACUCCAUUGACUCUGAGCCAGGAAGCCCUCUAUUGGAUGAUGCAAAGGUCAAAGAUGAGCCAGACUCUCCUCCUGUGGCGCUGGGCAUGGUAGACCGCUCACGGAUUCUUCUGUGUGUCCUCACCUUCCUGUGCCUCUCCUUUAACCCCCUGACUUCCCUGCUGCAGUGGGGAGGGGCCCACGACUCUGACCAGCACCCACACUCAGGCUCUGGCCGCAGUGUCCUGUCAUUCGAGUCAGGUUCUGGGGGCUGGUUUGACUGGAUGAUGCCUACUCUUCUCUUAUGGCUGGUAAAUGGUGUGAUUGUCCUGAGCGUCUUUGUGAAGCUGCUGGUUCAUGGGGAGCCAGUGAUCCGGCCACACUCGCGCUCCUCGGUCACCUUCUGGAGGCACCGGAAACAGGCAGAUCUGGAUCUCGCCAGAGGAGAUUUUGCAGCUGCUGCCGGCAACCUACAAACCUGCCUGGCAGUUUUGGGCCGGGCACUGCCCACCUCCCGCCUGGACCUGGCCUGCAGCCUCUCCUGGAACGUGAUCCGCUACAGCCUGCAGAAGCUACGCCUGGUGCGCUGGCUGCUCAAGAAAGUCUUCCAGUGCCGGCGGGCCACGCCAGCCACUGAGGCAGGCUUUGAAGACGAAGCUAAGACCAGCGCCCGGGAUGCGGCUCUGGCCUAUCACCGGCUGCACCAGCUGCACAUCACAGGGAAGCUUCCUGCAGGAUCCGCCUGUUCCGAUGUACACAUGGCGUUGUGUGCCGUGAACCUGGCUGAAUGUGCAGAGGAGAAGAUCCCACCGAGCACACUGGUUGAGAUCCAUCUGACUGCUGCCAUGGGGCUCAAGACCCGGUGUGGAGGCAAGCUGGGCUUCCUGGCCAUAAGAGACUCAUCCCUUGAUUCACUCAUUCAGCAAAUAUGACUGAGCACCGUCUCUAAGCAGGACAUUUGCCUUGUCCUCAGGGAGCAUAGUUGGCAAGGAAUCUAGACAGCAGCCCUUCUUGAGCUUGACAUUGAUCUUCUCAUGAGGAGGACUGGGCUCCAGGUGGGGAAAGAACCCCAUCCUCACUUGUGGGCUAGACGACCUGGGAGUCCACAGACACUGAAGACACAUCAUUCUUCCUAUUCAUUUCAACCUUCCCUCGACAGAUCUUCCUGGGACCAGGUCUUCAGGACAGUGUGAGCUAGGGUGAGCUCCUGAGCUGGUCUUGGGGGAAGUCAGGGUGGGCUUUCUGGGGAAGGUGAAUCUAGGCUGACAGCAGGAGGCAUUGAUGAGAUCUCUCUCCUUUUCAGUUUAUUGAAGUGCUCUGGGCUGAUGUCAUUACAUUUGUAACUUCCAUGCCCCCCAAAAAUGUUUUGAAGACAUUCAUUUUAUCAAAAUACAACAUACAUGCAGAAAAAUGCCCACAUUUUAACUUACGGCUUGAAGUGAAGUUACCCAUGCAACACCCACCCACAUCAAGAAGUAGAACAUUCCCAGCACCCCCAGAAGCCUUCUUGAGGCCCUCCCUGCUCUUCCUGCCCCAACCAAGGUAACCACUCUUCUGAAUUCUGUCACUGGAGUUUAAUCUGUCUAUUGUUCAUCAUUUCAGUAAACUUAUCAAAGUACAUGCUUAGAAGUCUGGCUGGGAGGGCCGGGCACGGUGGCUUACCCCUGUAAUCCCGGCACUUUGGGAGGCCAAGGCGAGCAGAUCACCUGAGGUCAGGAGUUCAAGACCAGCCUGACCAAUAUGAUGAAACCCUGUCUCUACUAAAAAUACAAAAAUUAGCCAGGCGUGGUGGCAUGUGCCUAUAAUCUCAGCUACUUGGGAGGCUGAGACAGGAGAAUCACUUGAACCCAGGAGGUGGAGGGUGCAUUGAGCGGAGAUCACGCCAUUGCACUCCAGCCUGGGCAACAGAGCAAGACUCCAUCUCAAAAUAAAUACAUACGUACAUACAAACAAAAAUUAGCUGGAUGUGGUGGUGCACACCUGUAAUCCCAGCUACUUGGGAGGCUGAGGCAGGAGAAUCGCCUGAACCUGGGAAGUGGAGGUUGUAAUGAGCCAAGAUUGCACCACUGCACUCCAGCCUGGGUGACAGAGUGAGUGAGACUCCGUCUCAAGAAAAAAAAAAAAGAUUACAAUAUGCAUGUCAAAAAGUAUACAAAUCAUAAAUACACAGUUCAGUGACUCCACAGAGUAAACACACCCUUAUAGCCAGCAGACAGAUCAAAGUACAGAACCAAGACCCCAGAAACUUCUCUUGGGCCCUUUGCAAUCACUAACCUGCCCCUUCCCCCAAGCCUUCCAGCCUUCCAAGGGUAACCACCAUCCUAGUCACCUCAGAUGCUUUGCCUCUGUUUAAACUAUAUUAAUAUAAGGAGAGUCUUGCAGUAUACACUGUUUUGUGUCUGACUUAUUUUGCUCAAUAUCAUGUGUAAGAAUCAUUAUGUUGUUAUGUAGAAUUAUAGAUUGUUCGUUCUCAUAUUUAUAGUGUUCCAUUGUAUGACUAGAUUAUUGCAGAUGAACUUUUUAGUUGUUUUCUGGCUUUGGUUAUUAUGAAGGGUGCUGCUGUGAACCUCCUUGUACACACAUCUUUCAGGAAACGUGACUGCAUUUUUAGGAAUGGCAUCGCUGGGUCAGAGGUUGUGCGUAUUUCCAAAUUGUUGGCCAUUCUCCACUCCAUCAGCAGUGAACAAGACUUCUAGUUCUACAUCCUUACCGAACACAUAUAAUGUCAAUUUUUUUAAGCCCUUCUAGUGUAUCUCAUUGUAGUUUUCAUUUGUACUUCCCAGGUGAUUAAUGAGAUUGAGCACCUCUUCUUACAUUUAUUGGCAAUUUGGAUAGUCUGUUUCGUUACAUUCAAUUCAAGUCUUACCUCUUUUUCAUUUGGACUAUCUGUCGUCUCAUUGAUUAGAGGAAUUCUUUAUUCUGGAGAUUACCCCUUUAUUGGAUAUAUGCUUUUCAGAUACCUUCUCCCACUCUGGGGCUUGCCUGUUCUGUCUUAAUGGUGUCUAGUGAGAGCACAAGCUCUUAAUUUCAGUGAAAUCCAGAUUAUUAGUCUUUUCCUUUACAGUUAGACAUUUUAAGUCCUGUUCAAUAAAUCUUUGUCCUACCUCAAAGUCAUGAAGAUAUUCUCCUAUGUUGUCUGCUAGACGCUUUAUUUUUUACUCUUUACACAUAUGUACCUAAUCCACCUGGAAUUAAUUUUUAUAAGAGUUGGAGGUAGGAGUGCAAGAUCUGUUUUUCUCCAUAAGGAUAUCUACCUGACGCAGAACCUGUUAUUUUAAAAACUAUCCUUCCCCUGCUGCACCAAGUGGCACCUUUUUUUCAUAAAUCAAGGAUCCGUGUACCGUGGGUCUGCCUCCAGAUCUAGUCUGUUCCACUGCACCAUCACCACCCAACCCUAACGGCUGAGUUUUCUCUUACGUCUUGAUGUCUGGAAGUGUUGGUCUUCCAGAUUUAGUGACUAACGAUGAAUCUUGGGUGUUUCUUUGUAGCCUCUUCAUUCUACAGAGGUACUUGAUGCUGCUGAUGGACAUUUGGGUUGUUUCCAGUAUUUGCCGUUAUAAACAGUGCUUUAGGGAACAUUUUUGUCCAUUGUCUUCAUGCACCUCCAUAAGAGUUUCCUCAGACCAAAUCUGUAGAGAUGGUGAUGCUGUGUCAAAGGAUAUAAAUAUUUGAAACUUAAUAGUAUUACCAAAUUUGCAUAUUCAGUAAGAUGGAAAAAGGAGAACUGUCAUCUUUAAAGUAACUGCUCUUCUCUGUUUACUUCUCUUGAGAGAGGAUAAAGAGACUCAGACAGUACUUUCUUAUAAAGGAAGAAGCUUUGAAUUUGGUGAGAUAUAUUUAGCUACAAAUGAGCCAGUUGUUGGGGGCAAGUGGAGGGCUGGCCUCUGUGAAAAUGGUUUAGACUAGAGGUUCCCAAACUUGCUCAACUCAUGACUCAAGAUUCCCAAACAUUCUCUACUCACUAUGUCUCAGUAAAUUUUUCAUGGCAUCCCUUAGCCAAAAGAAAUACCUAACGGUUCUGGUUUUCGUUUUUUGAAACAGUGUCUUGCUCUGUUGCCCAGGCUGGAGUGCAGUGGUGCAAUCACGGCACACUCUAGCCUCAACCUCUCUGGGCUCAAGUGAUCAUCCCACCUCACCCUCCCGAGUAGCUGGGACUGCAGGUAUACACCACCACACCGAGCUUAUUUUUGUAUUUUUUGUAAAGUCAGGGUUUUGCUAUGUUGCUCAGGCUGGUCUCGAACUCCUGGGCUUAAGCGAUCUGCCCACCUCAGCCUCUCAAAGUGCUGGGAUUAUAGGCAUGCACCACCGCGCCUGGCCUCUGUUAAGUAGUUAAGUUUGAACAUCCUAAUAGGUAUUUAAAUUGUCUUAACAGCUUAGUGGUCAUUUGAAAAAAUCAUAUGUCAAGUUGAAAGAAGAAAUAAUAUUUUUUGCUAGGAGUGGUAGCACACACCUGUGGUCCCAGCUCCUCAGGAGACUGAGGUAGGAGAAUCUCCUGAAACCACGAGUUUGAGGCUGCAGUUAGCUAUGGUCACACCUGUGAAUAGAGCCACUCCACUCCAGCCUGGACAACAUAGUGAGACCAUGUCUCUAUUAAAAAAAAAAAAAAAGAGGUUGGGCACGGUGGCUCAUACCUGUAAUCCCAGCACUUAAGGAGGCUGAGGCGGGUGGAUCACCUAAGGUCAGGAGUUUGAGACCAGCCUGGCCAACAUGAUGAAACUCCGUGUCUACUAAAAAUACAAAAAUUAGCCAGGGAUCGUAGCACGCACCUGUAAUCCCAGCUACUCGGAAGGCUGAGACAGAAUCACUUGAACCCAGGAGUCAGAGGUUGCCGUGAGCCGAGAUUGUGCCACUGCACUCUGGGUGACAGAGCAAGACUCUGUCUCAAAAGAAAGAAAGAGAGAGAAUAUUUUGGAUUCUUAAUAAUUUCUUAGAAAUCAUGGUUAUUAAGAAUCCAAAAUAUUCUUUUAUUUAUUUAUUUAUUUUUUGAGAUACAGCCUCACUCUGUUGCCCAGGCUGGAGUGGAAUGGCUCUUCACAAGCAUGGUGUCACUGUUUCUUACCAAUACAUGAACCUGUCAAGCACUGCACACCUCAAGCUUUGGAAUCAGACUAGCAACCAUCACUCUCUCUCUUUUCCACAUUGAUUUUCACACAGUACUAUGACAGAUAUCACAUCUCCAAAGGAAGCUAGUGUGGUCUCAAUGCUGAGGCUGCAUGCUCUCCCCAUCUAGUCACUUACAGUGCCCAGCUGAUGUUGAGCAUCACUGUUUUCCUCGAAAGUUUAAAAUAGCCAGUGGCUCCCUUGAUCACUUGCUGUGGCACCUCAGACUGCCUUGGCACACGAUUUGAGAGCCAUGGGGUUAGACCGAUGUUAGGGGACACAACCUGGGGUUGGGACUGGCCCAGGGAUACUGAGUGGCUCUCAGGAUCUAAACAGUUGUGGGGUUCUUGCCACAGCCUCUUUCACAUCAGGCAAUUAGCAGAUGAGUUACAGGGGGAGGCUCCUAGGCCCCAGUUGGGGAAGAUUCUGGUGUCUAUAAAAUUUAGGAAAACUUAAAAAAAAAUUUUUUUUUUUUUGGCUUGGGAUUACAAGCCAAGCCACCAGCGUGGCCAAGAUGGUGAAACCCUGUCUCUACUAAAAAUAUAAAAAUUAGCUGGGUGCGGUGGCGGGUGCCUAUAAUCCCAGCUACUUGGGAGGCUGAGGCAGGAGAAUUGCUAGAACCCAGGAGGCGGAGGUUGCAGUGAGCCAAGAUCACACCACUGCACUCCAGCCUGGGUGACAGAGCAAGACUCUGUCUUUAAAAAAAAAAAGAAAAGAAAAGAAUUAAGCUUAAAAUACAUUUUUACUUAGUGAUUUCCACAUUUGCCUUUCUGGUUCCUCUUGCCGUAUGACCUGGACUAGGCUUUGCUUCUACUUGUAACAUUUGGGCCCUCGUGAGGGACCAGUUGGUCCUCAGUUUCUCCUGGAGCAGCCACCAGGCUCCCUUGCUGAUUGGACAUGUGGAAUUGGCUGUUCUUGGAAAGAGAGUUGGAGUCAACCGUUCAAAUGUUCUGGGACCUCCGAAGCCCAGGAAUCACGCCACCACCCCCCAAUCUCCCUCCCUGCUCAGCUCCUCAACUGCUAUUCUCCCACCAUUGCAGUUAUCAGCUCAGAUUCAGUGAGUGCUUUGUGGAAGGUUGGCAGAGGGUCGCGAGGGUCCUCUACAUUUGUUCUCCAGUAUCCAGUAUCAACACUGGUUACCAAAGAGGAAGGACGGACUAUUGGUGCCCCUGGUCCCAGUGAUUAGAAAUGUAAGUGAAACACCCCACCUCAUCUCAUAAGCUGCUUUGAGAUUAUGAGUAUGUGUCUAUAGAACAGGUUGUUUUCUCUCAGACUCAGGCAGUGUCUCCAGGUUCCCCCUGGAGAGAGAUAGUCUUCUCUGUCUGUGUCCUCGAGUGGCACUCUGACAGUGCUAUUUCUGACCCUGGCAUUCAAGUCUUCUGAAGCCGUUACAUUCGCUGAUGGCUACUUAGAGCCCAGUAAAGGUCAGAACCAUCAGACUGAACCAGACCAUGAAACAGCGCUGCUCCUGUGGGGGCGAGGGCUGGGGUGUGGAAGCGAUGUCUGCGGGCCUCGGCCUGGCAGCCCCGCCCCUGGGCUCCCUGGGCUUUCUAUCUUAUGCUUCUCCCUCCCUCCUGUCUUCUGUCCUCAGUUCCUCACUCACCCUGGCCUGUUUCGGGGAGUGGUUAUGGGUUGGAAGUCAUGGGUGUUAGUGUGAAAAUACCCUCACUCAAAAAGUGACAGAACUGAAAACGUGGUAGAUGGUAUUGUCCCUGCAGUUCUUGUCAGUGGGGUCCUGGAAUGAUGUUAUCCCGGCAAGUGGAGGAGGGGCCCAGUGACCGGGGCCCUGGCUCUUUGAAUUGUCCCACAAAGAGGCUUUCCAGGUUCCCCCUCUGUUCUUUCUCGCAGGCUGGUGUUCACAUCAGGGGCUCAUGCAGGGGUGCCAUGGGGUUUCUGUAGGGGGCCGCCCUUGCAGGGCCAGCUUUGUGGGGGGAGUCUCUCAACCACCUGCACACAGAUACUUGCCUGUACAGGGCCUGGGCUGUCCUCCCAGCUGCCCCUUCACUCCAGUGCCAUCUGAUGUGACCCUGACGGCUGGCCAUGUGCCGAGCACUGUUCUAAACUUUACACGCAAAGUAAAAGUAAAAGAAAAAUUAGUCAAAGCAGAAUAAUUUUGCCUAAAAUAGUCUAAAAGAUAUGUAAUUAAAAUGACAUGAUGGGCCAGGCACGGUGGCUCACGCCUGUAAUCCCAGCACUUUGGGAGGCCGAGACGGGCGGAUCACGAGGUCAAGAGAUCGAGACCAUCCUGGCUAACACGGUGAAACCCCGUCUCUACUAAAAAUACAAAAAUUAGCCGGGCAUGGUGGCGCGCGCCUGUAGUCCCAGCUACACGGGAGGCUGAGGCAGGAGAAUGGCGUGAACCCGGGAGGCAGAGCUUGCAGUGAGUCGAGAUCGCGCCACUGCACUCCAGCCUGGGCGACAGAGCGAAACUCCGUCUCAAAAAAAAAAAAAAAAAAAAAUGACAUGAUAAAAAGUCCCAGGAUAGAAGGGGCUGCCUGGCUUGGCACUCUCGGGGCCGAGGGGAAAGUACAGCAGCCAGGGGGCCCCUGAGACCCCUCCUUGGGAAACCGCCUUCCUAGUUUACCCUGCAGGUUGAAUGCCAGUAGGAUCAGGCAGCCCCAGCAGGACAGGAUGCAGCAGGGGCCCCACGCGUGCCUUGUGGCUGCUCCCUGCCCUCCUGCUGGGAUGUGGACCUAGUCAGCAAGUCCAGCACACUCUACUGGUGGGCUUGCCCUAGUUUCCAUGGUGGGCUUUACUUUCAGGUACCUGUGGGAGUCCUAUCCCUGUGCUGAUCUUUCCCAGUCUCCCCCAAAGCCCACCUCCACCAUGGUGCUUUCUGCACCCCACAGUGGCUGCAGCCAGCAUUCUGCCACCUUGGUGUUACCCCUGGUCCUUGUCCUU